UCAAAAAAAAAAAAAAAAGAUUUUGUUUAGCUGUAUAUAGUUUCCUUAGUGAAGAAAAGGAGAAGAGAAUAAGAUAUUCAAGCAAGGUUAAAAUAUUGAAGCAGAAAUAAAAUAAGCUAAUAACGGGACUUGGAGGGUGAUUAAAAGGUAACAAAACACUGAAGGAAAGCAGUGACCAAAAGAACGUGAAAGACAGGGGUUACUGUGACAGAAUAGCCUCAGGACUUGCUGAUGAGUAGAUGUAGAAAGGAAGGAAGAGAGGGAGGAUCAAACCCCAUUCCAACCCCAAUCUUCCAGAAAAGCCUGAGGAUAAAUGAUGGGAGAGCGAAGAAUCCCUUUUAGCUGAAACAGAAGUUAUGAGAACAGAAGCAGUGGUAGAUGAAUGGUCCAUGUAUCUCUGAGCAGCUAUGAAGAAGCUUCCUGGAAAACAAUAAGCAAAGGAAAACAAAUGUGUCCCAUCUCACAUGGUUCUACCCUACUAAAGACAGGAAGAUCAUAAACUGACAGAUACUGAAAUUGUAAAGUUGGAAACUACAUUUUGCAAAGUCAUUGAACUCUGAGCUCAGUUGCAGUACUCGGGAAGCCAUGCAGGAUGAAGAUGGAUACAUCACCUUAAAUAUUAAAACUCGGAAACCAGCUCUCAUCUCCGUUGGCUCUGCAUCCUCCUCCUGGUGGCGUGUGAUGGCUUUGAUUCUGCUGAUCCUGUGCGUGGGGAUGGUUGUCGGGCUGGUGGCUCUGGGGAUUUGGUCUGUCAUGCAGCGCAAUUACCUACAAGGUGAGAAUGAAAAUCGCACAGGAACUCUGCAACAAUUAGCAAAGCGCUUCUGUCAAUAUGUGGUAAAACAAUCAGAACUAAAGGGCACUUUCAAAGGUCAUAAAUGCAGCCCCUGUGACACAAACUGGAGAUAUUAUGGAGAUAGCUGCUAUGGGUUCUUCAGGCACAACUUAACAUGGGAAGAGAGUAAGCAGUACUGCACUGACAUGAAUGCUACUCUCCUGAAGAUUGACAACCGGAACAUUGUGGAGUACAUCAAAGCCAGGACUCAUUUAAUUCGUUGGGUCGGAUUAUCUCGCCAGAAGUCGAAUGAGGUCUGGAAGUGGGAGGAUGGCUCGGUUAUCUCAGAAAAUAUGUUUGAGUUUUUGGAAGAUGGAAAAGGAAAUAUGAAUUGUGCUUAUUUUCAUAAUGGGAAAAUGCACCCUACCUUCUGUGAGAACAAACAUUAUUUAAUGUGUGAGAGGAAGGCUGGCAUGACCAAGGUGGACCAACUACCUUAAUGCAAAGAGGUGGACAGGAUAACACAGAUAAGGGCUUUAUUGUACAAUAAAAGAUAUGUAUGAAUGCA